AACACUGUGCCAAAAAAUAAUUGAGUGAUAGAAAAGUAUUAUUUUAAAAGGUCCACUUUGAAAGGGCUUAUCAGAAUCUCUGCAUUGAACAAGGGCAUAUGGACAGUCUUUAUUCAACAGACACUUCCUAAACUGUUCUAAAAUUUGUCUGCAAAUGGGAAAAGUCAAGAUACUAAUUUGGGUGAGAGGAAAAGAUUCCUCUUAGGUGUAGAUGAAUGAAUCAUGCAGUGAGAUUCCAGGCUAACUGUAGUUUCUUGAAUCUUAUUUGUUAAUCUGACUCACAGCUGAAAAGUAACCUGAUGAAUAACAGACUGAUCUUUAAUUAGAGAGAAAUGUUUUUAGGAGUCAGUUUUUUCAUUGCCUAAAAUGUUAAGUUGAAAUUUAAUGAAAUAAAAGUAAACAAACUGCAGAGUGACUGCAGAAUAAAGCUGUAUUAAAAUUCCAGCUGUUCUGUUGAAAUCCUUAUAAUGUUUGCAGUAAUGAUCUCUGUCCUUCAGUCCUGAUUUUUCACUCUUACUCUAAGUAAAUACUAUUUAUGAAUGCCAACUGUGUUAGAGCUUGGGAGCACAGGAUUUAAUAAGUGAACUAGAUGUACCUCUGCAAUUAAAUAACUGGAUAUUCUGGAGCCAGCUAGAUUCCCUGACAUUUUAGGCUGCCAAAGAGCAGAACCUGAUUUGAAUGUAGAUUGAGUCCAUACGUUAUAUAAAUAAGAAUGUAAGACAUUUAUCAACUGUUACGUGUCUCAGAGAGUUUCUACAGAAAGUCAACCCUUGAAAAUAAAUCUUUUCCUUUUAUUUUGGAUGUUUAAAAUUUUACAGGUGAAAAAAAUUCUUUGAAAUAUAAUUUCAGGCCGGGCACGGUAGCUCACGCCAGUAAUCCCAGCACUUUGGGAGGCCGAGGCGGGUGGAUCACUUGAGGUCACGUGUUUGAGACCACCCUGACCAAUGUUGCGAAACUCCAUCUCCACUAAAAAAAAAAUAGAAAAUUAGCUGGGCGUGGUGGUAUGCACCUGUAAUCCUAGCUACUCUGGAGGUUGAGGCAGAAGAAUCGCUUGAACCUGGGAGGCAGAGGUUGCAGUGAGCCGAGAUCACGCCACUGCACUCCAGCCUGGGCAACAAGAGCGAAACUCCAUCUCAAAAAAAAAAAAAAAAAGAAAUAUAAUUUCAUGUGGAACUAUGUGUUGGUGCCUGUAUUCAAAUAUGUGAAGAAAUGGCCUUUUCUUCUAAUGCAGCGAGUUUGCUACUUUGUACCAAAUAAUUUUUUUGCUUGGCUUUGAGAUAACUUUAUGAUUUUAUUUUGAAACUACAAGCAAUAAAUUUUAGUAGGGGAAAUGUGUACAUUCUUAUUAAACAACUUUUUACUGGUUUUAUGUAACUAUUCUAGUUAUUAGAACUGAAAUUCCAAGGGCUUAGGGAUAGGUUGGAAAAUAAGUUUCAUUUUAUGCUAGUUUAUUUUAGGAAGCUACUAGGCAAAUAGCCACUUAUCACUUAAUAUCAAAAUAAUUUUUUUUUUAAGACAGAGUCUCACUCUGUCAGUUAAACUGGAGUGCAAUGGCACAAUCAUGGUUCAUUACAGUCUUGACCUCUGGGCUCAAGCAAUCCUCCUGUCUCUGCCUCCUGAGUAGCUGCAAUUACAGGUGUGUGGCACCAUGCCCAGCUUAUUUUUGCACUUUUUGUAGAGACAAGGUUUCACUGUAUUGCCUUUUGUAGAGACAGGGUUUCACUUUGUUGCCUAAACUGGUCUCAAACUCCUGGGCUCAAGCAAUCCUCCCACCUCAGCCUCCCAAAGUGCUGGGAUUACAGGCAUGAGCUACCACACCUGGCCUUUUCUGGGGGGACUGGUUGGGGAUGGAGAAUAGGAUCUCACUUUGUUACCCAAGCCGGAGUGCAGUGGCACAAUCAUGGGUCAGUGCAGCUUCAUCUUCCUGGGCUUAUGUAAUCCUCUUGCCUCAGCCUCCCAAGUAGCUGGGACCACAGGUGUGUGUCACCAUGACCAGCUAAUUUUUUUUUACUUUUUAAUUUUUUUAGAGAUGGAGUCUCACUGUGUUACCCAGGCUUAUCUCAAACUCCUGGGCUCAAGUGAUCUUCCUGCCUUGACCUCCCAGAGUAUUGGCAUUACAGGAGCAAGCCAUUGUGCCUGGCCUGCUUUCUUUCACUAAUAGGCUUAAUCAACUUUAAUAAAAUUUAGAUUAAGAUCUUUAAAAUUUUUUAAAAACUGAUUUUAUCUGUCACUCAUAUUCUUUGUCCAUUCCAUUUACUAUGCAUUCUUAUUUAACAGGUGAUAAUUUUAUAUUCCAUAAGUGCUUAAACACCAUUCAUUACUAAACUACAUUUUUGUUUAAUUUCACAUAAUUUUUAUAUAAGCAGUACUCUUUCUCAGUUUCUCUUGAACAUUCAACUCAUUAGUGAGUGGUUUUCCCCAGUCAUUUCCAUUUUUCUUUAUUUGGCUCUGAUAGUUUUCUGUUUUUGUUUUUCAGAGAUAAUCCUUUACUAUACUAAAUUCUACGUGAUUAUAUUUUCCACCUCUAUUUGCCUAUAUUUAUCUGCUGUCUUUUCCUUUUCCAUAUAUGGGCUUAUUUUUUUUUUUCCCUCUUCUUCCUUUUCUACCUUUGGUAUUUAAAAAGUUACUUAGGACUGAGUGCACUGGCUUACGUGUGUAAUCCCAGCACUUUGGCAGGCUGAGGCGGGAGGAUUGCUUGAGCCCCGGUGUUCAAGGCUGCAGUGAGCUACGAUGGUGCCCCUGCCACUCCAGCCUGGGCAACAGAAUGAGACCCUGUCUGGGUUUGGGGGAGAAGUUAUUUACAAUGUUUUGAAAAUAUCCUUUGGCCCAGGCAUGGUGGCUCACACCUGUAAUCCCAGCACUUUGGGAGGCCGAGGCAGGUGGAUCACUUGAGGUCAGAAGUUUGAGACCAGCCUGGCCAACAUGGCAAAACCCCAUCUCUACUAAAAAUACAAAAAUUAGCCAGGCAUAGUGAUACAUGCCUGUAAUCCCAGCUACUGGUGAACACUCCAGCCUGGUGACAAAACAAGACUUUGUCUCAAAAAAAAAAAAAAAAAAAAAAAAAAAAAAAAAAAAAAAAGAAAGGAAAAGAAAAUGACCCUCAGAUAUAAUUCUAAUAUCACCAGUUGGCCUUUCUUGACAUCUCUUUUAGUCUUCUCUCUUUUUCAGAAAUGUGAGUUCUUUGCGAAAUGUUUUGAACUGAAUUUUAGGUCAUUAAAUUGUGAGUUUUGGAAUAUAGUGGAAGGGACAUGUGAGUGUUUUAGAUUAGUAGAAUGACAAUCAUUUCAAUUUCUUUAAGUAUUUUCAUCUUCUGUUUUUAGGAAUAGUGGACUCAUCUUUGGUUAAAUGAAGGUUUUGCAUCCUGGAUUGAAUAUCUGUGUGUAGACCACUGCUUCCCAGAGUAUGAUAUUUGGACUCAGUUUGUUUCUGCUGAUUACACCCGUGCCCAGGAGCUUGACGCCUUAGAUAACAGCCAUCCUAUUGAAGUCAGUGUGGGCCAUCCAUCUGAGGUUGAUGAGAUAUGUGAUGCUAUAUCAUAUAGCAAAGGUGCAUCUGUCAUCCGAAUGCUGCAUGACUACAUUGGGGAUAAGGACUUUAAGAAAGGAAUGAACAUGUAUUUAACCAAGUUCCAACAAAAGAAUGCUGCCGCAGGUAAUCUUUAAUAGCUUGAGAUAGAAAUGGAGAGAAAGUAUUGUCACUCUAUCCAGGCUGGGACAUUUUAUUUUUGUUCUGAAUACUUAACUCAAGGUCAGGAUCCAUGUAAUAAAUAAAUUAGCCUUAUUUGAAGCUGUGUUCAGGUUGAAUAUCUCUAAUCUGAAAUUUGAAAUGCUCCAGAAUCUGAAACUUUUUCUUUUCUUUCUUUCUUUUUUUUUAAUUAAAGUUCUAGGGUGCAUGUGCACAAUGUGCAGGUUUGUUACAUCAGUAUACAUGUGCCAUGUUGGUUUGCUGCACCCAUUAACUCGUCAUUUACAUUAGGUAUUUCUCCUAAUGCUAUCCCUCCCCCAGCCCCCUACCCCAUGACAGGCCCUGGUGUCUGAUGUUCCCCGCCCUGUGUUCAAGUGUUCUCAUUGUUCAAUUCCCACCCAAAAUCUGAAACUUUUUGAGUGCCAACGUGAUGCUCAAAGGAAAUGCUCAUUGGAACAUUUUAGAUUUUGGAUAUUGCAAUUAUAGAUGCUCAGCUAGUAAGUAUAAUGCAAAUAUUCCAAAAUCCAAAAGAAAUAUGAAAUUCAAAACAUUUCUGGUCCCAAGCAUUUUGGAUAAGGGACACUCAACCUGCAGUAAGUCAUAGGGUCAACAUGAAUCAGGACUCAUUAUCCCUUUGGUCAUCCUCCAGCAUUCUGCUUUCCAUAACUGAAUAUUUUGCCAACUUAAAGAGUCUGGGCCGGGUGUGGUGGCUCACGCCUGUAAUCCUAGCACUUUGGGAGGCCAGGAUGUGAGGACUGAUUGAGCCCAGGAGUUCAAGACCAGCUUGCAACAUAGCGAGACCCCACCUCUACAAAAAAUACAAAAAUAUUAGCCGGGUGUGGUGGUAUGUGCCUGUAGUCCCAGCUACUCAGGAGGCUGAAGUGGGAAGGGUCACUUGAGCCCAGGAGUUUGAGGUUACAGUGAGCAAUCGUGGCACCACUGCACUCCAGCCUGGGCAACAGAACAAGAUCCUGUCUCUGAAAAAAUAAAAAAUCAAGGGAAUAGUCAUGUGUUGCUUAACAACAGGGAUAUGUUCUGAGAAAUAUGUUGUCAGGCAAUUUCAUCAAUAUGUGAACAUCAUAGAAUGUACUUACAGAAACCUACACAGUAUGUCCUAGGCUAUAUACACCUAGCCUACAUGGUAUAUACCCUGUUGCUCCUAGGCUACAAAAUACCUGUACAGCAUGUUACUGUACUGAAUACCAUAGGCAAUUAUAACACAAUAGUAUUUGUAUACCUGAACAUUUCUCAAUAUAGAAAAGUUACAGUAAAAAUAUGAUAUUAAAGAUGCUCCAUCAGCUGGCUGAUAUGCCUAUAAUCCGAGCACUUUGGGAGGCUGGGGCAGGUGGACUGCUUGAGUCCAGGAGUUUGAUACCAGCCUGGGCACCAUGCCAAUACCUCGUCUCUAUAAAAAGUACAAAAAUUAGCUGGGUGUGGUGGCAUGUGCCUGUAGUCCCAGCUACUUGGGAGGCUGAGGUAGGAGGAUCAUAGUUUCAAAGUGUGGCACUUACUGGUUCUCCACUCACUCCCUCCUGCCGUCUUGUGAAGAAGGUGCCUGCUUCCCCUUCCCCUUCUGCCAUGAUUGUAAGUUUCCGGAACUGCAAGUCAAUUAAGCCUGUUUCCUUUAUAAAUUACCCAAUCUCAGGUAUUUCUUUACAUCAGUGUGAAAACAAAUGAAUACAGUCCCCUUCCCUGAGGUGCCUUCUCCUUAGGCAACCAGCUGCCCCCAUGCUCCUCUUCUGCCCCCCUGGUAUUUCCUUUCCCCUCAUGAGGCCCAAGUGAUCCACAUGGCCAGCCACAGCCCCAUCCUACUGCAGGCCUGUGUGGCUGCUAGAGAGGCCAGGCUCCUUUCCGCACCCCGAGGCUGCCCGAUAUGCUUUCUGCAUCCUGUAGAAAACUGACCCACUAUUCUCAUACUGGUGCAACUUCUUCCAUUACCUCAAAACUGGACAACGUGAACUUGUUUCUUGUCUCUUCUUGCUAGGGCUGUCACUGGGACAGUCCGAGAUGGGGGGGUGGGGGGAGACAAUGGAUGAAUGGAUGGAUGAAUGGACAGUAGUCCAGGGAGAUGUCCCUGUGUGUCCUGAACUGGGACCUUCCUCCAAUGAGAAGCCUUCCUGAGUGAGUUUAUACAGUCAUCCCUUGGUAUCCAUGGAUUAGUUCUAGGGUCCCCGGGGAUGCCAAAAUCCAUGGAUCCUCAAGUCUCUGACAUAACAUGGCCUAGUAUUUACAUAUCAGCUAUGCACAUCCUCCCGUAGACAUUAGACCAUCUCUGGAUUAUUCAUGAUGUGUAAUACAAUGCAGAUGCUACAUAAAUGGUCGUGAUACUGGAUUCUUUAGGGAAUAAUGACAAGAACAAACUCUGCACAUGUUCAAUAGAAACAUAACCGUCCAAUUUAUUUUCUGAAUAUUUUCCAUCUGCUGUUGCUGAAUCUACAGAUGCAGAGCUCCUGGAUACGAGAGCCAAGUGUGCUUUGAGAGUAGGGUGGGUGAGGUUGCUAAUGAGUACAGGGGAGCAGGUGUUGAUCAGGAGGACCCUGCACUGGGGCAUCUGGACGUCCUGCCUCAGGACUUGAGACUCCAGUUGGAUGGCACAGGCAGACUCAGCCCAGGUCAAAGCCGUCCCCUUGAAGUUUCUUUUUAUCCCAAGCUCUUUCUGGCCCCUGGAAUUUGGCAUCCCCUAGGCCCUGUGUGGAAGGACAGAUGAACCAGGUUUUAGAUAACAUGUCUAGAAGAGUGAGCCCCUACUGUGUGCCCGGCACUUUCCCCACAGGAUCCUCUAGCUAGAAUAUCCAAGGGUCAUGGAGAGAAAUACCCAGUUAAAAUAUCAGAAAUGAAAAAGCGAUACCAUUAGAGACACUAAAAAGACCAUUAGGUAAUAGUACUAGCUUUUGUAUUCUGAGAUCCAACAGCAGCAGUCACUUCCCUCCACCGCUAUGUGUAUCCCAGGACCACCCUGGGCAGGGAGGGCUGAGGUUAGGGAGCAGCCAUGGAUGCUCUGAUGCUGGCCCUGGGCCUCGGGGGUGACAGUGAUGAGGAACUGGGUGCACACAUGAGUGGGGCAGCCGGGCCUGGCCAGAGAAGCAGCACACACGUGCACAGAUGUGUUUACCCACAUACACAUGUGCACGCACGUGCACAAACACAUUGCAGGCAGGCAUGUUGACGCCUCAGGCAGCGGAGGACCCUGACUCUGGGUGCUGCUGACCCGGGCAAGGCCCCACUGUGAUUCGUGCCAUGACCUCAGAAUGUCACUGGUGCUUAGCACCUAUCUGCUCUCUGGUCUGCCUCAGUGGUCUACAGCAGUUACACACAGGCAGUGGUAUCUGUGAGCAGCUCUGUGGACUCAAAGGUUUUCUCCCUGAGAGGCAUGACCCAGGCCAGCUGAUUCAUCAGAAUCAGGAUGGACGUGGUAGAGGUCGCGGGCAGUUGGUGGGCACAAGAGCGAGAGGACAUCAUUAUGAAAUACGAAAAGGGACACCGAGCUGGGCUGCCAGAGGACAAGGGGCCUAAGCCUUUUCGAAGCUACAACAACAACGUCGAUCAUUUGGGGAUUGUACAGUCCUGCCCCUCCUGGGAGUCAGCCCCACAGGAAGGCCCUUGUCCUCCCUUCCCUGUGCCUUCUCCUGGGCUGAGCCCUGAGCUGGAAAGGGACAGAGCCAGUCCUUUCUGGGGGUCGGCACCCAGGCUGGGGCCGCUCCAGGCCCCGUGCAGUUCCUCAGCUCUGCCUGGGUUGCCUUACAGUGAGACGGAGCUGCCUCCUCUGACUGCGCGGGAGGCGAAGCAAAUUCGGCGGGAGAUCAGCCGAAAGAGCAAGUGGGUGGAUAUGCUGGGAGACUGGGAGAAAUACAAAAGCAGCAGAAAGCUCAUAGAUCGAGCGUACAAGGGAAUGCCCAUGAACAUCCGGGGCCCGAUGUGGUCAGUCCUCCUGAACAUUGAGGAAAUGAAGUUGAAAAACCCCGGAAGAUACCAGAUCAUGAAGGAGAAGGGCAAGAGGUCAUCUGAGCACAUCCAGCGCAUCGACCGGGACAUAAGCGGGACAUUAAGGAAGCAUAUGUUCUUCAGGGAUCGAUACGGAACCAAGCAGCGGGAACUACUCCACAUCCUCCUGGCAUAUGAGGAGUAUAACCCGGAGGUGGGCUACUGCAGGGACCUGAGCCACAUCGCCGCCUUGUUCCUCCUCUAUCUUCCUGAGGAGGAUGCAUUCUGGGCACUGGUGCAGCUGCUGGCCAGUGAGAGGCACUCCCUGCAGGGAUUUCACAGCCCAAAUGGCGGGACCGUCCAGGGGCUCCAAGACCAACAGGAGCAUGUGGUAGCCACGUCACAACCCAAGACCAUGGGGCAUCAGGACAAGAAAGAUCUAUGUGGGCAGUGUUCCCCGUUAGGCUGCCUCAUCCGGAUAUUGAUUGACGGGAUCUCUCUCGGGCUCACCCUGCGCCUGUGGGACGUGUAUCUGGUAGAAGGCGAACAGGCGUUGAUGCCGAUAACAAGAAUCGCCUUUAAGGUUCAGCAGAAGCGCCUCACGAAGACGUCCAGGUGUGGCCCGUGGGCACGUUUUUGCAACCGGUUCGUUGAUACCUGGGCCAGGGAUGAGGACACUGUGCUCAAGCAUCUUAGGGCCUCUAUGAAGAAACUAACAAGAAAGCAGGGGGACCUGCCACCCCCAGCCAAACCCGAGCAAGGGUCGUCGGCAUCCAGGCCUGUGCCGGCUUCACGUGGCGGGAAGACCCUCUGCAAGGGGGACAGGCAGGCCCCUCCAGGCCCACCAGCCCGGUUCCCGCGGCCCAUUUGGUCAGCUUCCCCGCCACGGGCACCUCGUUCUUCCACACCCUGUCCUGGUGGGGCUGUCCGGGAAGACACCUACCCUGUGGGCACUCAGGGUGUGCCCAGCCCGGCCCUGGCUCAGGGAGGACCUCAGGGUUCCUGGAGAUUCCUGCAGUGGAACUCCAUGCCCCGCCUCCCAACGGACCUGGACGUAGAGGGCCCUUGGUUCCGCCAUUAUGAUUUCAGACAGAGCUGCUGGGUCCGUGCCAUAUCCCAGGAGGACCAGCUGGCCCCCUGCUGGCAGGCUGAACACCCUGCGGAGCGGGUGAGAUCGGCUUUCGCUGCACCCAGCACUGAUUCCGACCAGGGCACCCCCUUCAGAGCUAGGGACGAACAGCAGUGUGCUCCCACCUCAGGGCCUUGCCUCUGCGGCCUCCACUUGGAAAGUUCUCAGUUCCCUCCAGGCUUCUAGAAGCAUCUGGGCCAGGGCUCAUGGCUGGAUAAUUUCCCUAGGCUUAACAACCCAAGCAAGCUUCGCAUCCUCGUUUUAUUUUUGGUUAAACUUAUGAAAAUGUAUUAAGAAAGAGUGCAGCUCGAGAGAGAUUCAGAGAUGGAACACACCAGACCCCAGAUCACAAAGCCAACCAUGCCCAGCCCCUCCCAGCACCCCCAGCCCCACGACCAUCGUUCUGAAUUCUGACGACACCGUGAGCCUGCCUUUGUACUUCAAACUCAUGGAAGGAUAACCACCUUCAUGUUUUGAAAUAAAUGUUUCCUGUUGAAAUGA